AAUAUCAACUGAUCAAAGACCAUUUUUCAUCCAACCAACACUCUUUCUACUACCUUAUUUUAAAAACAAUAUGACUACCAGAAAUUUUAUCAAGAUUAUGUAACAUUAAAUAUACACAAAUACAUUGGAAGAAAGUAUUUUAGUGGUUAUAAAAAAUCUGCUGCAUAUUCUUCUGAACAUUUUUAUACAUUUUAAGCAAUGUAUUAAGCAUUUGAUAAAAGGAUUGUUUUGUCAAUAUAUCUCAACCUUACCUAAUGUGAGAUUUUAAACAGCAUUCAAUAAUAGUAAUAACAUAACAUUUUAUAGCUCCUUCUCCUACAUUAUUUGUAAAUCUCACUUAAACUGCUAUCUUAUUUUUCUUUUCGUAGUAUGCAUCCUAUGUUUCCAAAAAUAUCAUAUGAAAGACAAAUUGAAAGUUAACUAUUAAUUAAUUAUAAUCAUUGCAGUUUUGUUCUGGUGACCCUAACUAAUGAAAACUUUGCUGUAAAAAGUGGGGUGCUGCUGUAACAAACACCUAAACGUGUGGAAGUGGCUUUGGAACUGGGUAAUUGAUAGAGACUGUAAGAGUUUUGGGUGAAUGGUAGAAAUAUGGGUGUUCAGGGUGAUUCUGGUGAGGUCACAGAGAGAAAUGAGAAAAAUGUCAUUGGAAACUGGAAGAAAGGUGAUCCUUGUUAUAAAAUGGGAUAAAACUUGAUCUCACAAGUAAUGGAUUUGGAUAUUUGGCUGAGAAAAUUUCUUAGCAAAAUGCUGAAGGAGCAGCUUGAUUUCCCCUAACUGCUUAUAGUAAAAUGCAAAAGAAGAGAAAUUAAUUGAAGGAGUUGUUAUGCAAAAAGGAACCAAAAUUUAAAUAUCUGGAAAAUUCUCAGCCUAUCCAUAUGGCAAAAAAUGAGAAAUUGUGUUAUAAAGAGAACAACCAAUUGAUAACAAGAUCAUGGGUGCUACUGAUGGACUUAAUCAGCCAUUUCAGCAGAAGGUAGGAGUAGAGAUAUAUUAUACCAGCAAAUACACUUCCAGUUUGAACUGAAGGAGACAGAGAAAGCAGGACAGAAUGAGAAAAGGAUACUGGACUUUCUGGAUUCUACAGAACCAGACCAUAGAGCUAUUUGGCUGUGAAUGUGUACUAUUCUUCAGGGAAAGGAAAGAAUGCCCCCAAAAGUGAUACAGAAGUCAUCAGGGUUGCCACUUCCACCACAGACCCAGAGGCCAAGGCAGUUUCCUUUUUGGUUUCAAAGGGCAAAACUGUCUCUCUGGUUUUAGUGAGCCCUCAGGAUGACCCUGCCUAGUGUCUCAGAAGCAGAGCUAUCCUCACAGAAAGCUGUGUGGAUGGAGCCCUUAGAGAGAGCAGGCUGUCUUGCAGAGCCCUAGAACCUGCCAUUCCGUGGACCUGGAAGGCAGAGCAUCAAACCAAACAGAGCUAUUCUCAAGCCUUAUAAGCCUUAAGAUGUGACAGAAUUUACCUUAAUAAGUUUUGGAUUUGCUUGGGACCCAUCACCCUUGCUUUCUUUCCUAUAUCUCCUUUUUGGAAUAAGACGUCCAUCCUAUGCCUGUCCCACCAUUGUAUUAUGGAAAAGAAACAUGUAGCUCAACUGGUUUCACAAGUUCACAGCUGGUGAUGAAUUUGCCUUAUCAUGAAUCACACCUCUAGUCUCAUCUACGUCUGAUUUGGACAAUGUUUAGAGAUUGAGAAUUUAUCACAAGUUGAUGGUCCUCAAGUGGAAGAGCAACUUCUUUCAACCACAGUUCAGCCAAAUCUGGAGAAGGAGGUCUGGGGCAUGGAGAAUAACUCAUCAGAAUCAUCUUUUGCAGAUUCUUCUGUAGUUUCAGAAUCAGACACAAGUUUGGCAGAAGGAAGUGUCAGCUGCUUAGAUGAAAGUCUUGGACAUAACAGCAACAUGGGCAGUGAUUCAGGCACCAUGGGAAGUGAUUCAGAUGAAGAGAAUGUGGCAGCAAGAGCAUCCCCGGAGCCAGAACUCCAGCUCAGGCCUUACCAAAUGGAAGUUGCCCAGCCAGCCUUGGAAGGGAAGAAUAUCAUCAUCUGCCUCCCUACAGGGAGUGGAAAAACCAGAGUGGCUGUUUACAUUGCCAAGGAUCACUUAGACAAGAAGAAAAAAGCAUCUGAGCCUGGAAAAGUUAUAGUUCUUGUCAAUAAGGUACUGCUAGUUGAACAGCUCUUCCGCAAGGAGUUCCAACCAUUUUUGAAGAAAUGGUAUCGUGUUAUUGGAUUAAGUGGUGAUACCCAACUGAAAAUAUCAUUUCCAGAAGUUGUCAAGUCCUGUGAUAUUAUUAUCAGUACAGCUCAAAUCCUUGAAAACUCCCUCUUAAACUUGGAAAAUGGAGAAGAUGCUGGUGUUCAAUUGUCAGACUUUUCCCUCAUUAUCAUUGAUGAAUGUCAUCACACCAACAAAGAAGCAGUGUAUAAUAACAUCAUGAGGCAUUAUUUGAUGCAGAAGUUGAAAAACAAUAGACUCAAGAAAGAAAACAAACCAGUGAUUCCCCUUCCUCAGAUACUGGGACUAACAGCUUCACCUGGUGUUGGAGGGGCCACGAAGCAAGCCAAAGCUGAAGAACACAUUUUAAAACUAUGUGCCAAUCUUGAUGCAUUUACUAUUAAAACUGUUAAAGAAAACCUUGAUCAACUGAAAAACCAAAUACAGGAGCCAUGCAAGAAGUUUGCCAUUGCAGAUGCAACCAGAGAAGAUCCAUUUAAAGAGAAACUUCUAGAAAUAAUGACAAGGAUUCAAACUUAUUGUCAAAUGAGUCCAAUGUCAGAUUUUGGAACUCAACCCUAUGAACAAUGGGCCAUUCAAAUGGAAAAAAAAGCUGCAAAAGAAGGAAAUCGCAAAGAACGUGUUUGUGCAGAACAUUUGAGGAAGUACAAUGAGGCCCUACAAAUUAAUGACACAAUUCGAAUGAUAGAUGCGUAUACUCAUCUUGAAACUUUCUAUAAUGAAGAGAAAGAUAAGAAGUUUGCAGUCAUAGAAGAUGAUAGUGAUGAGGGUGGUGAUGAUGAGUAUUGUGAUGGUGAUGAAGAUGAGGAUGAUUUAAAGAAACCUUUGAAACUGGAUGAAACAGAUAGAUUUCUCAUGACUUUAUUUUUUGAAAACAAUAAAAUGUUGAAAAGGCUGGCUGAAAACCCAGAAUAUGAAAAUGAAAAGCUGACCAAAUUAAGAAAUACCAUAAUGGAGCAAUAUACUAGGACUGAGGAAUCAGCACGAGGAAUAAUCUUUACAAAAACACGACAGAGUGCAUAUGCGCUUUCCCAGUGGAUUACUGAAAAUGAAAAAUUUGCUGAAGUAGGAGUCAAAGCCCACCAUCUGAUUGGAGCUGGACACAGCAGUGAGUUCAAACCCAUGACACAGAAUGAACAAAAAGAAGUCAUUAGUAAAUUUCGCACUGGAAAAAUAAAUCUGCUUAUCGCUACCACAGUGGCAGAAGAAGGUCUGGAUAUUAAAGAAUGUAACAUUGUUAUCCGUUAUGGUCUCGUCACCAAUGAAAUAGCCAUGGUCCAGGCCCGUGGUCGAGCCAGAGCUGAUGAGAGCACCUACGUCCUGGUUGCUCACAGUGGUUCAGGAGUUAUCGAACAUGAGACAGUUAAUGAUUUCCGAGAGAAGAUGAUGUAUAAAGCUAUACAUUGUGUUCAAAAUAUGAAACCAGAGGAGUAUGCUCAUAAGAUUUUGGAAUUACAGAUGCAAAGUAUAAUGGAAAAGAAAAUGAAAACCAAGAGAAAUAUUGCCAAGCAUUACAAGAAUAACCCAUCACUAAUAACUUUCCUUUGCAAAAACUGCAGUGUGCUAGCCUGUUCUGGGGAAGAUAUCCAUGUAAUUGAGAAAAUGCAUCACGUCAAUAUGACCCCAGAAUUCAAGGAACUUUACAUUGUAAGAGAAAACAAAGCACUGCAAAAGAAGUGUGCCGACUAUCAAAUAAAUGGUGAAAUCAUCUGCAAAUGUGGCCAGGCUUGGGGAACAAUGAUGGUGCACAAAGGCUUAGAUUUGCCUUGUCUCAAAAUAAGGAAUUUUGUAGUGGUUUUCAAAAAUAAUUCAACAAAGAAACAAUACAAAAAGUGGGUAGAAUUACCUAUCACAUUUCCCAAUCUUGACUAUUCAGAAUGCUGUUUAUUUAGUGAUGAGGAUUAGCACUUGAUUGAAGAUUCUUUUAAAAUACUAUCAGUUAAACAUUUAAUAUGAUUAUGAUUAAUGUAUUCAUUAUGCUACAGAACUGACAUAAGAAUCAAUAAAAUGAUUGUUUUACUCUGCAUUGAA